AGGCUCCUGGCGCGCCCCGCAUGCCUCCAGCACGUUUACCUUUCCGAAGUGGCAGGAAUGGGGAAAGCGCACGCUUAGGAGAGCUUCAGACAAGCUUCCCUCUUCCUCCUCCACGACCAGAAGCGGAAAGGUGCUCCCGGACCGAAAGGGAAAGAAGAACAGAGGCUUCUCCCGAAAAAGCCACACAUUCCUGCCCAAGAUCUUCUUCCGCAAGAUGUCAUCCUCAGGGGCCAAGGACAAGCCUGAGCUGCAGUUUCCCUUCCUUCAGGAUGAGGACACAGUGGCCACGCUGCUAGAGUGCAAGACGCUCUUCAUCUUGCGCGGCCUGCCAGGAAGCGGCAAGUCCACGCUGGCACGGGUCAUCGUGGACAAGUACCGUGAUGGCACCAAGAUGGUGUCGGCUGACGCUUACAAGAUCACCCCCGGCGCUCGAGGAGCCUUCUCCGAGGAGUACAAGCGGCUCGAUGAGGACCUGGCUGCCUACUGCCGCCGCCGGGACAUCAGAAUUCUUGUGCUUGAUGACACCAACCACGAACGGGAACGGCUGGAGCAGCUCUUUGAAAUGGCCGACCAGUACCAGUACCAGGUGGUGCUGGUGGAGCCCAAGACGGCGUGGCGGCUGGACUGUGCCCAGCUCAAGGAGAAGAACCAGUGGCAGCUGUCGGCUGAUGACCUGAAGAAGCUGAAGCCUGGGCUGGAGAAGGACUUCCUGCCGCUCUACUUCGGCUGGUUCCUGACCAAGAAGAGCUCUGAGACCCUCCGCAAAGCCGGCCAGGUCUUCCUGGAAGAGCUGGGGAACCACAAGGCCUUCAAGAAGGAGCUGCGACAAUUCGUCCCUGGGGAUGAGCCCAGGGAGAAGAUGGACUUGGUCACCUACUUUGGAAAGAGACCCCCAGGCGUGCUGCAUUGCACAACCAAGUUUUGUGACUACGGGAAGGCUCCCGGGGCAGAGGAGUACGCUCAACAAGAUGUGUUAAAGAAAUCUUACUCCAAGGCCUUCACGCUGACCAUCUCUGCCCUCUUUGUGACACCCAAGACGACUGGGGCCCGGGUGGAGUUAAGCGAGCAGCAACUGCAGUUGUGGCCGAGUGAUGUGGACAAGCUGUCACCCACUGACAACCUGCCGCGGGGGAGCCGCGCCCACAUCACCCUCGGCUGUGCAGCUGACGUAGAGGCCGUGCAGACGGGCCUUGACCUCUUAGAGAUUCUGCGGCAGGAGAAGGGGGGCAGCCGAGGCGAGGAGGUGGGCGAGCUAAGCCGGGGCAAGCUCUAUUCCUUGGGCAAUGGGCGCUGGAUGCUGACCCUGGCCAAGAACAUGGAGGUCAGGGCCAUCUUCACGGGGUACUACGGGAAAGGCAAACCUGUGCCCACGCAAGGUAGCCGGAAGGGGGGCGCCUUGCAGUCCUGCACCAUCAUAUGAGUGUUCUCACCACCACUUAUGCCCCUAGAAGGGAAGGGGAGAGGGAAACGUGCCCUCUGUUUGAUCCUUGUUUUGUGACAUUUUUUUUUUUUUUUUUUUUACUCAAAGUUAACCUACCUGUAACUUUUUAAAAACUUGUAAAAUAACUGACCCUCCCUUCCUGUCCGCCCUCUUCCCCUCUAAUGCUCACGCUCCCAACACAAGGUGGGCAGGGAGGCACCAUUCAGGAACCUGGACCAAAGCUGACGAGGCUGGGCCAAGCCAGGGAUGGGGCCACAGCCAGAACCCCGAGCCCUACUUCCAGGUUCUGGUUAGCUCAGCCCCAGCCCAGCCCAGCUGCUCUGCCCAGAGCUGGGUGAGUGGGGAGACACCUCAGAGCCCCGCAAAACCCACUGACCGGAGGCAAAAGGCAGUGGGGCUGGGGGUAGUUUUCCAUGGUCACAGAGAACUAGUGGUGGCUCUGAGAAGGGGAGGACCUCUGGGCUUUGAUUCCAUCUCCUUGUCUUUUUUCUUUGUUUUUAGAGACAGGGUCCUGCUAUUUCCCAAGCUGGAGUGCAGUGGUGCGAUCAUGGCUCACUGCAGCCUCGAACUCCUGGGCUCAAGCAAUCCUCCUGAGUGAUCCCAUUUCUUAAUCAGUGUAGCCCCAAGAAGGCUGGGGCUAUUUACCAGGGUAGAAAAAGGAGCUUACCUCCCACCUUUGGUCCUAAGUCCCUGCCCCCUCCCCUUCACACCAUAACUAGGUAACAGUUUGAUAACUAGGGAAGAAAGCAGAACAGUUAAGCAGCCGCCACAUCCCCGCUGGCUGGGGGCCUCACUCCAGGAAGGGGCUGGACUGGCUGUCCUUUCCAGUGGCCUGGCUCCGCUGUGUGGAUGGGGAGAUCGGGGCCAGAGGCAGAACCCUGGUGAGGAAGCUCCAGUCCUGCUCUCUACCCAGCCCAUCUUGCCUCCAUGGUGCCUCUGGAGGCCUCUGGGCCUCCUCUAACAGGGGCUGGUGGGCACCAAGAGCCAAUGGAGUAGACCCCUGGCUGGUAAGGGCCAAGUCCCACCGGUUGCUUCUGGGAAGGGGUUUCUAACACUAGUCUGUGUGCUGUGGUUCCUGGGGUGCCCUCCACUGCCCUCUGUUCAGUAACAGGGCCUUGCUAAUCGGGUUGUCACUCAACAAAAGUGCUUUGGAUUUAAGUUACUAUCCUGGCUUUGCCCAACCUCAGCAACCUGUAAGACUGAUAAUGAAAUAAAUCAUGUUAAUCCUAGCUGUGUGCAGUCUCUCUUACCCUUCUGUGCCCAGCUCAGUCUUCCCUAGGGCUGGGUGUAUUAGGACUGGCUUUGUCCCACAGCUUGGGGCCAUCGGUCCUGUCUCCCCUCUGCUGGCCGGGCACAGCUGUGGUGAGGUUGGGCAGCUGAACAGUGUUGGCUUUCAUGAGGAGGCAGAAAGCAGAGGCUGGCCUCAGACUCAUACAGAAGGUGGGGGUUGGCUGGGUACGAGGGAUGUGGAGCACAAAAGCCUCUCAUCCCCCAUUAACCAGGGCACCAAGCCCACAGGUGUCCCCAGCCCACUGGAUCAGAAAGAGUUCAGUAAGACCGGAAGCUCCUGGUAUGGGUUUCUCCCAGUUCUCUAGGGAAGGCCACCUGCAGGUCACUGAAACUUCAAGCACCAGGGAAGAUCUAACAUUUGAGUCCCUUCCAGGCCAUCAGAGGCCUAGUCAGCCACAUGGGAAACUUCCAAGACCUGACUCAGGCAUCAUUCCACCAUGGCUAAGGCACCAGCCGGGGAAGACUUGAAAGAAAGGGGCAGGAGCUCAGAUGAAGAGAAAUCCUAAGUUACCUUUCUAGGUCAAGGCCUGUCCCUGGCCAUCUCUGAACUUCAGCUAGAGCUUCAAGUCUGUGCCUGGAGCUCCUGGGAAGGCUACUCACCUUGAACACCACGCUUGACAGGACAGCAUGGUGCAUGCCGCUGCAUCCGUGAGCAGUGUGUCUCCUGCAUGCAGAAAGGGAGCAGAGAAGGCCAGGGGCUUUUGCUAAAAAUAGUGGCCAGACCAGAGCUCUGGAGCCACCUGUCCCACCUCAAAUGGGUCUGGGGGUCAGGAGGCAGGGUUUUAUCUCUGUCUACCAUCUCCCUCGAACCCACACUGCAACAGGAACUGUGAGAGUCUUUGUAAGUAAACUGCCCUGUCUAGGUCAGUACCCACCUGAGCUUUGGACGCACACAGCUUUUAGUACCCACCUGAGCUUUGGACACACACAGCUUCUAGUGAUUUCUGGGGCCCCACCGUAAAGUGAGCAUGCUUUCUGAACUCGCUUCUCUGUGACUGAUGUUAGGCUGGGCCCAGAGGCACAGCCGGGGCCUGCCUAGCACUCACAUGCUGGACAGGUCUGGGAGAGGCAGAGUGCCCCACCUGCCACUAGGCUGGGUGCCCACAGCCCGCAUGCAGCAGCUUGCUGCACCCCAAGUCCAGGUCGGGCUCAGCUCUGGCUCACAGACUGGAGACAAUGCAGAUGCCAGAGCAAAGGGCCAGGAAGGGUCAAAACAUUUUAUUCUCUUUUUUUUUUCUUUUUUAAUAAAGUUAAACAGUAAAACAAAAAUUCACAAGCUGCCUCCCUGUCCACCCCCGCCUCCCUCCCCUGCCCUCGGUCUUCGGCAUUGGUUCCCUUUGCUCCACCCCACUCACAGAGACACAGGGCAUCCAACUGAGAAAACGAAACUGCUCUAAGCACACGGAGACGUGAUGAAGGGAGGAGGUGAACUGUUUCCACAUUCAAGAUUAAACUGAGUGAAUCUGCAUUUUCUGGGUUCUGGGUGGUUGCCCUUCAUUAGCCAAAUUGAAAAAAGAAAUUCCCUGGACCAGAUGCUGAAAGAGAAAAGAGGGGUUGGUAGUUGGCUAUGGAUUUUCUAAGGAAGAUCACUUUGCUCUGAUUAUGGAAAAGUCUUCAAGGGCUGCUUCAAACUCAAACACAGAGAGAAACUCUAUGGGUAUCAAACAGCUCAGGCUGUUUUUGGGUGCAAGAGGGAGCACGUGACUGUAUUAUACAUGGGUAGCUUCUGACCUCAGCAUUAUCUAUAUAGUACCUUUGCUCUUGCAGAGAAGCCUUGGUACUAGGCAGUUAGAGAUGCCUCCCUGACCCUGCAGAGAUGCGGUGGCUAAAGGUCCCAAGGCAAGGGGUGCCUGGGAACCUUCCUGUCUUCAUCCUUAGCAACAGCCGAGUGGAUAGAUGCCCUGCUAGAUGAGAAUUCAGCUGCCCCCGCUCAUGGGCCCCUCUGACUCCCAAAGAGCUGCCUAAGAGGCAAUGAGUGUGUUGGCUUGUGAUCUGGGAACUCCCAAGAACAGCAGGCCCACCUACCUUCAAAGCUGAAGCCGCCAGGACCGCCAAAGAAUGCCUUGAAGAUAUUGUUUGGAUCAAAAUCUGUAGAGCAGGGCAAGUAACAUGGAAGGGAAGAAAAGGUGAAAAAUUAGAAAUGUUCGAAGAGAACUGAUGACACUGAGAACAGAUCUCCAAAGCUUUCCUGGAGAGUCUCACUCCCCUCCUUUCCCAACACUUCAGACUGCAAGUGAGCAAACCUGCCCCAUCCCGUGCAAAACAUGCUACCUGAUCCCACUCCUAGGACAUGUUCCCUUCUCCUUCCAACUGCUGCCCCAAAGGAAGCUUUCUCUGCUUCAGCUUGCUUCAUUGGGCUGUUUUCUCAACAAAUGGAAUGCCAUUUGCACUUACACAAGACUUUCCCCAUACUCUGUCUCCCUAUAAUGCUGGAGCGGCUACUAAAAAGGAUAAAAUGUAUCACUUAAAUGUUACCAAAAAUAAAUAUAAGAGCAAGAUCUAGGA